UGAGUGUGUAUCCCUCUUUAAAUGAGGAAUUGUAAAAGGCAUAACAAACGGCUUUGCAUGGGCCUGCGUUUUCUUUUAUUUUGAAAUUUGGAGGCCCUAGAUAUUUUCCCAGUAUCUAUGAUUUAUUUAGGAAUGGAUUUUAUAGACUCCACUCGCUACCCACCCCACCCCCAAGAAAAGCAAAACAACGAAAUGACAUAAAAAGAUGUUGUUGGAGGUUUUAACCCAACAGGUAAGUUUCUUUUAAGCAAGAUAUUUAUGCCGAUUUAGAUUUCACUUUUACUAUUCUGGUUUUAUUUCACUUAAUGCAGUCACGUUUUUUCAGGCAGCUGAGAGCCACAUUGCUGGGGAGUUCCUGAUGCUGCGGGGUUAUAUAAUCUGACUUAAACUGGGCCUCAACCCAGAGAGGUCAACAUGUUCUUUAUUUAAUUGGUCUUUUAGGCAUUUAAACGCACAUGCAUAUUUGAAAGAAAAAGUCUAUUAGAAAGGUUAUGUAGAGUCAGCUUGAAUAUUUCAUCAAGCAAAUUCAAAUGGAUUCUUCCCCUCUCCCUGUUGUUCUGGGGCGGAGGGGGGAACAGGCUUUCUUCCUCCUGAGCACUGUUUUGAGGUGAGCAAACGGACUGAAGGGAAGCUGUGUCCAGAGGGGUCGCCGAUUUUUUUUUUUUUUUUAAUGUUUCAGGGAGCUGGUGAACCGCGCAUCCGGCGGUUGUGCCCAGGAGUGACAUUUUUUCCCCAAGAGUGGGGACACGGAUUGAAGGCCGGAGUUCCAGCCAGAACUCUGGUUCUGCGCGGGCCAGAUGGAGCUGUUUCCGUUGCACAGACGACGUCCACAACUUCCCAUCGCUGGGCGUGGCGAGGAGGGGCUGCCCCGGGCUGCGCGCCCUUUACGCCCAGGGACAGGGCCUGGGGACAUCUGAGGGAAGUGAUCCGGGGGGCUGCCGCCCACCGAGAGGGGCAGGCUUCGACAGCGCCACCCUGCCGCACAUGCCCGGCGCCUCGCCGGCCCUCUCCAAAGGUGUCCAGGGGCUGCGCCGCGACACUUUCCACCGAGCGUCUGCCAGCAGCUGGACCCCGCUCUCCAAUGGCCGCCGCCGCCAAGUCCCCGGGGCUCCCGCACUCCGGGCCGGGCGCGAAGGUCACCGCCCUGCACCACCUUGGGCUGCGCGUCCAUUUCCAAGAGGCAGGCAGUGGGGAGAGGGGAGCGGGGGCGCUGUGUUCCCUUUCCCUCUCAUCACUAACCUCCCACCUUCCAGCGGUUUCUGAAAGUGAGUUAAGGGGAGCAAAAGUCACUUCUCUUUCCGGAGCCAUCAGAAGAGUUUAGGAAAAGGUCAGAGGGUCUCUCUGUCUCUCCGUCUCUUUCUCUCCAACCCCCUCCUCUCUCUCUCUCUCUCUCUUUUUCUCUCUCUGUGUCUCCUUUUGUCCCUGCCUAUCCAUUUAUUGAUUGACUAUCUUUCUAAUCUAUUGAUUAUUACCUGCCCAUUCAUUCCCCUUUCCAUCCAUUUCCAAAAUAAGAAAUCGCCCUCUGCCCUGCUUCUCCUCCCAGUGUGAAAAAUACACUCAGCCUUUGGGCUCGGCCCGCAGAACAGAACUGGAUUUACAUUUACAAAGCAACAGGGUUGAGGUGAAGGCAGCUGACGGGCGCGCACCCCCUCCUCACCUACUCCCCGACCCUUGCCCCGCUACGCCUCACUAGAGGUGCCUCGUGGUGGUAUUGAAAUCACCGAGAACCGAAUUCACUGAAUUAAGGAAGGAUUGUUGCUGCAACUAAGUUCAC